ACAUUAACCGGCAGGAUGUCGGAGGUGCGGCUGCCACCGCUACGCGCCCUGGACGACUUUGUUCUGGGGUCGGCGCGUCUGGCGGCUCCGGAUCCAUGCGACCCGCAGCGAUGGUGCCACCGCGUCAUCAACAACCUCCUCUACUACCAAACCAACUACCUUCUCUGCUUCGGCAUCGGCCUCGCUCUCGCCGGGUACGUGCGGCCACUUCAUACGCUCCUGAGCGCGCUGGUAGUGGCGGUGGCCCUCGGCGUGCUGGUGUGGGCAGCUGAGACCCGCGCAGCUGUGCGCCGCUGCCGCCGCAGCCACCCUGCAGCCUGCCUGGCCGCAGUGCUUGCCGUCGGCCUCCUGGUGCUCUGGGUCGCGGGCGGCGCUUGCACCUUCCUGUUCAGCAUCGCCGGGCCGGUGCUUCUGAUCCUGGUGCACGCCUCGUUGCGCCUGCGCAACCUUAAGAACAAGAUUGAGAACAAGAUCGAGAGCAUUGGUCUCAAGCGGACGCCAAUGGGCCUGCUACUAGAGGCACUGGGACAAGAGCAGGAGGCUGGAUCCUAGGCCCCUGGGAUCUGUACCCAGGACCUGGAGAAUACCACCCCACCCCCAGCCCAUAAUUGGGACCCAGAGCCCUUUCCCAGCACUUAAAACAGGAGCCUAGAGCCCCCUGCCCAAACAAAACAGGACAUCUGUGACCGCCCUACCCCCACGCCAGCCCCAAACUAAGAUAUCCCUCACACCCAGCCCCCAUUACCUAGGGACAAGAGUCUUCCCCAGCCUUGAACCCAGGACCAAGAGCCACCUACAUCCAGCCCCAAAACUGGCUUCAGGCCAGAGCAUCCAUGGCCAAUUUCAAAUUGUGAACCCAGAGACACUCCCAUCCACCCUUCUCCAUGCUCAUCCCCAAACUGGGGCCUGGGGCAAGGCACUCUCAAAUCUUGAACCCUGGACCAAAGCUUUUCCAGACCCCACCCUACCUUCCAACCCAGGUCAAGACAUUGCCAAAUCUUGAACUCAGAACCCAAGUGUUCCAUGCCCCUGUGUGGAUGGAGUCGGGUAUCCUGACUGUUGGACCCCUGGUCCAGGUGAUCCCGACCCUCACCAGUCCCAUUUGCCUCCCUCCAGCUCUGCUUAGGCAUUUUGCCCCUCACCCCAAUGUUCCACACCAUCGACAACCAAGGGGUGAGGUGGGGACAGGCCUCAGCAGGGAAUGGGGCGUAUAUGUUAGUGUUGCUGCAACAAUAAAGCCUGUUGCAUCUCUCAUGCCAA